ACCAGCCUGGCCAACACGGUGAAACCCCAUCUCUACUAAGAAAAAAAUAGAAAAAGUAGCCAUGCGUGGUGGCGGGCACCUGUAGUCCCAGCUACUCGGGAGGCUGAGGCAGGAGAACUGCUUGAACCUUGGAGGCCGAGGUUGCAGUGAGCCGAGAUCGUGCCACUGCACUCCAGCCUGGGUGACAGAGUGAGACUCCAUCUCGAAAAAAGAAUAAAAGAAAAACAAAUGCUGGACCGAGAAUUCAUUUAACACAGAGUUGACAGCACACUGAGGAAAUCUUUGCGGAUUGCCCUAGGACGGGGCAUUGUGAAGCUAAUAGGCAGUACUGUCUAAUUUCUCAAUUUCCUUUCAAUAAUAGCGGAACAUGCCGGACGUGAAUGAGGCCGCCCGGCAUUUUCCUUCCCUUAUUCAAUUUACGUGCUGCCUUUUGACAUCUGACUGAUGUGGUAAGGAUGCACCCCACCCUAGAACGUGCUUUCAAGAAGAAAUUGAGUUUCUCUUAAUCAUGAGAUCCAUCUUGCUAAUUGAUUGUCCUGUAAACAGUGUGGGGCAGCCCAUGCUGGCUUUGUUUCAGUGACGCUGGGGAAAAGCCACACGUCUCUGCUGUCAUUUUGAUGUCCACGCAGCUGCCUUUCCCAUCUGGGUCACUGGAGGGUGGGAACAGCCCUUAACCUCUGCCUCCCUUUCCCAGGACAGAGCAUUCGCCUCCCUGCAAGCCUGGCUCGGACUUGCCUGGGACCUGCCAGGAGCUGAACGUAGUUUUCUUUCUCCCAUGGGAAAUAAUUUUCUUGGGCGCGGUGGCCGUGGGUUACCAGUCCCUGGCUGUCAAAGCUCACGCGUGUGUGACAGUGACGCUGUUGUUAGGCACGCCGGAGUUUCCAUUACGGAGUCCGUGUAUCUGCCGCGGGGACUUUCCUAGGAGAGGCGUCACUGCAACAGGCCUAGGAGGGGACUGGCUUGGGAAAAAAAGAAGAAUAUUGUGUGUGAUAUGCAGGAACUGAGAAAUAGCCUCAAACUUUGGAACAAAUACCGAAUUUCCAACAUUCCAUCACUAAUAUUCCUCGACGCCACCACUGGGAAGGUUGUGUGCAGGAACGGGCUGCUGGUGAUCCGAGAUGACCCAGAAGGUCUGGAGUUCCCCUGGGGACCGAAACCCUUCAGGGAAGUCAUUGCAGGGCCCUUGCUUAGAAACAAUGGGCAGUCUCUGGAGAGCAGCAGCCUGGAGGGGUCUCACGUGGGCGUCUAUUUCUCCGCACAUUGGUGUCCGCCCUGCCGAAGCCUCACCCGGGUCCUGGUGGAAUCCUACCGGAAGAUCAAGGAGGCAGGCCAGAACUUCGAGAUCAUCUUCGUUAGUGCAGACAGGUCGGAGGAGUCCUUCAAACAGUACUUCAGUGAGAUGCCCUGGCUCGCCGUCCCCUACACGGAUGAGGCCCGGCGGUCGCGCCUCAACCGGCUGUACGGAAUCCAAGGCAUCCCCACGCUCAUCAUGCUGGACCCGCAGGGCGAGGUGAUCACGCGGCAGGGGCGGGUGGAGGUGCUGAACGACGAGGACUGCCGGGAGUUCCCCUGGCACCCCAAGCCCGUGCUGGAGCUCUCCGACUCCAACGCCGCGCAGCUUAACGAGGGCCCCUGCCUCGUCCUUUUUGUAGAUUCUGAGGAUGACGGAGAGUCCGAGGCGGCCAAGCAGCUGAUUCAGCCGAUAGCUGAGAAAAUCAUUGCCAAGUACAAAGCCAAAGAGGAGGAGGCACCCCUUCUGUUCUUCGUAGCCGGGGAGGAUGACAUGACUGACUCCCUGCGAGAUUACACCAACCUGCCUGAGGCUGCCCCUUUGCUCACCAUCCUGGACAUGUCAGCCCGGGCCAAGUACGUGAUGGACGUGGAGGAGAUCACCCCCGCCAUCGUGGAGGCCUUUGUGAAUGACUUCCUAGCAGAGAAGCUCAAACCGGAGCCCAUCUAGCGUGGCUCCGGCCUCCUGAGACGUUAUUUAAAACUCAGCCUUCUCCUCCUCCCCCUCCUUCCUUCCGCCCUUGGACUUACCCAGCGUGCCCCGAAUCCCACCACCCAAGUGUCCAGCCUCUCUGUGGUGCCUUGUUUCUGCAGUAAACUCCUCAGCCAGCACCCUGGGGUGUGGAAUCAGCAGCGGCAGAGUCCACCGUGUUUGGAGACUCUGUUUGGGAGCACGGGAUGGCCGGGGGCCCGGCCAGAGCGGGGCUGCAUGGCUUUCGCAAAGUCACUAGCUUUUGGUGAAGGAUCUGCCAGGGUGUCCUGGGCAGAGUGAGCGUGGAGGGCCGGUGGGUCCCGCUCGGGCUCUGACUCUGACGUCGGCACACACGGCCCCGGACGGCCAGAGGGGAACCGCCGGGUGACACCUGCGUGGAGGCUGAGCUGAGAAAGGGCCUCCGCUUAGAGCUGCGGGUGAGGACGUCCUUUUCUAAGCAACACAGUCUUCCUCGGUCUGAGAGAAAAGCAGCCCACUCUUGUGUUCUCAGGCAGGGGAUCUCCAAAUGCAAAAGGAAGCUUGUAGAGGUUUUUUGGGUGAGAAGAAAAAUGUAGCUAAGGUAAUGGUUCAUAUCAUACAAACAGCUCCCACGAUCCUGAAAUUCUGUUAACGAAUCCUUCUCUUUGGACAUCUUCCCAAGAAACUUAGCCCUGAGUCCUAGGAGGAGCACCUCUGCACCAGCACGGACCUCUCGCUCCACCCAGCUCUGUGCCCAAGGCCCCUGAUCUCUGCUGAGGUGCCCACACCCACGUUCGAUCACCCCUGCCAUUCCCUUUUAUUUUCUUUUUUUUGAGAUGGAGUCUUGCUCUGUCGCCCAGGCUGGAGUGCAGUGGCACCAUCUUGGCUCACUUCAACCUCCGCCCCCAAGGUUCAAGUGAUUCUCCUGCCUCAGCCUCCCGAGUAGCUGGGAUUACAGGCACCCGCCACCGUACCUGGCUAAUUUUUGUAUUUUUAGUAGAGAUGGGGUUUCACCAUGUUGGCCAGGCUGGUCUCGAACUCCUGACCUCAGGUGAUCCACCCGCCUCGGCCUCCCAAAGUGCUGGGAUUACAGGCGUGAGCCGCCGUGCCCGGCCCCCUUUUCUUUUCAAAGCAGAACUACAAAGAUGAGAAAUUACCAGAAGCCUCGCCUUUUCCUAAGCACCAGCGGAAGGAGCUGUGCCCCGGGAUGGAGUGAGGGUGGAGGGCGCGUCAGCCACGGGUGGGCCUUGUGUCGCCUUGUAUCGGCCCAGGUAGGUUGUUGGCCUCUUACUUGGGCUGACCUGACCCCCGAAAGAGAAACAGACAACUCUGUUCUCAGGAUUGGGGAUGGACGGCUUCGGCCAAGCGUUUUAGCCUCAUUCACUCAGGCCCCACUCAGCACUCUGCCAGCCAAGACCAUUGAUUUGGAAAAUCCGGUCCCCACCCGCUAAUGAGCUGUUGACACUGUUGUUCCUUGCUGAAUUGGAUUGUUGACUUGUAGUUCAGAGGCGUACAACUAGUUGGCGAUUAGACUUGUUAUGUGAUGUUACCAGCCUGAAAUGCGAUCACCCCGUAGGAAAUAAAGCAGGCAUCUCUGGACCUCAUCCACCCUGGGCCUCUGCUGUCCUUGAUCACAAAA